GAUCCCGGUGCCAGGGACCCUGCCCAGUUCCAGGCGUCGCCCUGACCCAGAAACGACUGGGCGCCGCCGUCCUGGAAAGGCCCCAGCGCACGGACAUCUGAGGAGCUGUUUCCGUUCCUCUGCCCGCCAUGCCGUUCCUGGAGCUGGACACGAAUUUGCCCGCCAACCGAGUGCCCGCGGGGCUGGAGAAACGACUCUGCGCCGCCGCUGCCUCCAUCCUGGGCAAACCUGCGGACCGCGUGAACGUGACGGUACGGCCGGGCCUGGCCAUGGCGCUGAGCGGGUCCACCGAGCCCUGCGCGCAGCUGUCCAUCUCCUCCAUCGGCGUAGUGGGCACCGCCGAGGACAACCGCAGCCACAGCGCCCACUUCUUUGAGUUUCUCACCAAGGAGCUAGCCCUGGGCCAGGACCGGAUACUUAUCCGCUUUUUCCCCUUGGAGUCCUGGCAGAUUGGCAAGAUAGGGACGGUCAUGACUUUUUUAUGAUUGGGCACGGAGGGAUCCAGGGCAUCUGUGAACUGGCUGCUUCUUCCAGAGAGAUCUCUUGGCAGAGUGAGGGCCUGGAGAUAACCAGCUUUGGAUUAUCCCGCAUGCAACAUUCCUGUGAUCACAUAAUCCUCUUCUUCAUCCUCAUAUGAAAUAAAUGAAGAGAGCUUCCUCAUUCAAA